AGAAGUGAAGAUGGCGGCGGCAGCUUCUCGCUAGUGACGCGCGGUGCGGGCUCAUCUCCUUCCCCUCCUUCCUCACCUCCCCUAGUCCGGACCCCGUCCGCCGCCGGGACCAGACCGUCCCCGUAGCCCGCAGCCAGCAGCCGCCCCUCUCCUCCCCCGGCCGCCCCUCUCCCAACGCCCGUCUGCCGCUGGCCGGCGGCGCGCCCCUGGUCCCGGCCGCCUGCCUCGCACUCCGCGCUGUCGCCGGGGGAGCGGGUGGCGUGUGGAUUCGCCCUCCUGCCCGCCCCUCCGGGCCGCGGACACACGCCCGGCAGGGAGGCGGCGGCGGCCCCUGCGUAUUUGCUUCCCUCCAUUUGGGGACUGGGAGGCGGCGGCGGCUGUGGGUUUUGGGGAGGGGUAGAGGGCUGGGGGGCGGGCGAGAGCGGGAGGGGGCCGCCCUCGAGUGGAGGACGAGAAGGAAAGCACCAUGACGUCCAUCCAUUUCGUGGUUCACCCGCUGCCGGGCACCGAGGACCAGCUCAAUGACAGGUUACGAGAAGUUUCUGAGAAGCUGAACAAAUAUAAUUUAAACAGCCACCCCCCUUUGAAUGUAUUGGAACAGGCUACUAUUAAACAGUGUGUGGUGGGACCAAAUCAUGCUGCCUUUCUUCUUGAGGAUGGUAGAGUUUGCAGGAUUGGUUUUUCAGUACAGCCAGACAGAUUGGAAUUGGGUAAACCUGAUAAUAAUGAUGGGUCAAAGUUGAACAGCAACUCGGGGGCAGGGAGGACGUCAAGGCCUGGUAGGACAAGCGACUCUCCAUGGUUUCUCUCAGGUUCUGAGACUCUAGGCAGGCUGGCAGGCAACACCUUAGGAAGCCGCUGGAGUUCUGGAGUGGGUGGAAGUGGUGGAGGAUCCUCUGGUAGGUCAUCAGCUGGAGCUCGAGAUUCCCGCCGGCAGACUCGAGUUAUUCGGACAGGACGGGAUCGAGGGUCUGGGCUUUUGGGCAGUCAGCCCCAGCCAGUUAUUCCAGCAUCUGUCAUUCCAGAGGAGCUGAUUUCACAGGCCCAAGUUGUUUUACAAGGCAAAUCCAGAAGUGUCAUUAUUCGAGAACUUCAGAGAACAAAUCUUGAUGUGAACCUUGCUGUAAAUAAUUUACUUAGCCGGGAUGAUGAAGAUGGAGAUGAUGGGGAUGAUACAGCCAGCGAAUCUUAUUUGCCUGGAGAGGAUCUUAUGUCUCUCCUUGAUGCCGACAUUCAUUCUGCCCACCCAAGUGUCAUUAUUGAUGCAGAUGCCAUGUUUUCUGAAGACAUUAGCUAUUUUGGUUACCCUUCUUUUCGUCGUUCAUCACUUUCCAGGCUAGGCUCAUCUCGAGUUCUCCUUCUUCCCUUAGAGAGAGACUCUGAGCUGUUGCGUGAACGUGAAUCCGUUUUACGUUUACGUGAACGAAGGUGGCUUGAUGGAGCCUCAUUUGAUAAUGAAAGGGGUUCUACCAGCAAGGAAGGAGAGCCAAACUUGGAUAAGAAGAAUACACCUGUUCAAAGUCCAGUAUCUCUAGGAGAAGAUUUGCAGUGGUGGCCUGAUAAGGAUGGAACAAAAUUCAUCUGUAUUGGGGCUCUGUAUUCUGAACUUCUGGCUGUCAGCAGUAAAGGAGAACUUUAUCAGUGGAAAUGGAGUGAAUCUGAGCCUUACAGAAAUGCCCAGAAUCCUUCAUUACAUCAUCCACGAGCAACAUUUUUGGGGUUAACCAAUGAAAAGAUAGUCCUCCUGUCUGCAAAUAGCAUAAGAGCAACUGUAGCUACAGAAAAUAACAAGGUUGCUACAUGGGUGGAUGAAACUUUAAGUUCUGUGGCUUCUAAAUUAGAGCACACUGCUCAGACUUACUCUGAACUUCAAGGAGAGCGGAUAGUUUCUUUACAUUGCUGUGCCCUUUACACCUGCGCUCAGCUGGAAAACAGUUUAUAUUGGUGGGGUGUAGUUCCUUUUAGUCAAAGGAAGAAAAUGUUAGAGAAAGCUAGAGCAAAAAAUAAAAAGCCUAAAUCCAGUGCUGGUAUUUCUUCAAUGCCGAACAUCACUGUUGGUACCCAGGUAUGCUUGAGAAAUAAUCCUCUUUAUCAUGCUGGAGCAGUUGCAUUUUCAAUUAGUGCUGGGAUUCCUAAAGUUGGUGUCUUAAUGGAGUCAGUUUGGAAUAUGAAUGACAGCUGUAGAUUUCAACUUAGAUCUCCUGAAAGCUUGAAAAACAUGGAAAAAGCUAGCAAAACUACUGAAGCUAAGCCUGAAAGUAAGCAGGAGCCAGUGAAAACAGAAAUGGGUCCUCCACCAUCUCCAGCAUCCACGUGUAGUGAUGCAUCCUCAAUUGCCAGCAGUGCAUCAAUGCCAUACAAACGACGACGGUCAACCCCUGCACCAAAAGAAGAGGAAAAGGUGAAUGAAGAGCAGUGGUCUCUUCGGGAAGUGGUUUUUGUGGAAGAUGUCAAGAAUGUUCCUGUUGGCAAGGUGCUAAAAGUAGAUGGUGCCUAUGUUGCUGUAAAAUUUCCAGGAACCUCCAGUAAUACUAACUGUCAGAACAGCUCUGGUCCAGAUGCUGACCCUUCUUCUCUCCUGCAGGAUUGUAGGUUACUUAGAAUUGAUGAAUUGCAGGUUGUCAAAACUGGUGGAACACCGAAGGUUCCCGACUGUUUCCAAAGGACUCCUAAAAAGCUUUGUAUACCUGAAAAAACAGAAAUAUUAGCAGUGAAUGUAGAUUCCAAAGGUGUUCAUGCUGUUCUGAAGACUGGAAAUUGGGUACGAUACUGUAUCUUUGAUCUUGCUACAGGAAAAGCAGAACAGGAAAAUAAUUUUCCUACAAGCAGCAUUGCUUUCCUUGGUCAGAAUGAGAGGAAUGUAGCCAUUUUCACUGCUGGACAGGAAUCUCCCAUUAUUCUUCGAGAUGGAAAUGGUACCAUCUACCCAAUGGCCAAAGAUUGCAUGGGAGGAAUAAGGGAUCCCGAUUGGCUGGAUCUUCCACCUAUUAGUAGUCUUGGAAUGGGUGUGCAUUCUUUAAUAAAUCUUCCUGCCAAUUCAACAAUCAAAAAGAAAGCUGCUGUUAUCAUCAUGGCUGUAGAGAAACAAACCUUAAUGCAACACAUUCUGCGCUGUGACUAUGAGGCCUGUCGACAAUAUCUAAUGAAUCUUGAGCAAGCGGUUGUUUUAGAGCAGAAUCUACAGAUGCUGCAGACAUUCAUCAGCCACAGAUGUGAUGGAAAUCGAAAUAUUUUGCAUGCUUGUGUAUCAGUUUGCUUUCCAACCAGCAAUAAAGAAACUAAAGAAGAAGAGGAAGCGGAGCGUUCUGAAAGAAAUACAUUUGCAGAAAGGCUUUCUGCUGUUGAGGCCAUUGCAAAUGCAAUAUCAGUUGUUUCAAGUAAUGGCCCAGGUAAUCGGGCUGGAUCAUCAAGUAGCCGAAGUUUGAGAUUACGGGAAAUGAUGAGACGUUCGUUGAGAGCAGCUGGUUUGGGUAGACAUGAAGCUGGAGCUUCAUCCAGUGACCACCAGGAUCCAGUUUCACCCCCCAUAGCUCCCCCUAGUUGGGUUCCUGACCCUCCUGCGAUGGAUCCUGAUGGUGACAUUGAUUUUAUCCUGGCCCCCGCUGUGGGAUCUCUUACCACAGCAGCAACCGGUACUGGUCAAGGACCAAGCACCUCCACUAUUCCAGGUCCUUCCACAGAGCCAUCUGUAGUAGAAUCCAAGGAUCGAAAGGCGAAUGCUCAUUUUAUAUUGAAAUUGUUAUGUGACAGUGUGGUUCUCCAGCCCUAUCUACGAGAACUUCUUUCUGCCAAGGAUGCAAGAGGGAUGACCCCAUUUAUGUCAGCUGUAAGUGGCCGAGCUUAUCCUGCUGCAAUUACCAUCUUAGAAACUGCUCAGAAAAUUGCAAAAGCUGAAAUAUCCUCAAGUGAAAAAGAGGAAGAUGUAUUCAUGGGAAUGGUUUGCCCAUCAGGUACCAACCCUGAUGACUCUCCUUUAUAUGUUUUAUGUUGUAAUGACACUUGCAGUUUUACAUGGACUGGAGCAGAGCACAUUAACCAGGAUAUUUUUGAGUGUCGAACUUGUGGCUUGCUGGAGUCACUGUGUUGUUGUACGGAAUGUGCAAGGGUUUGUCAUAAAGGUCAUGAUUGCAAACUCAAACGGACAUCACCAACAGCCUACUGUGAUUGUUGGGAGAAAUGUAAAUGUAAAACUCUUAUUGCUGGACAGAAAUCUGCUCGUCUUGAUCUACUUUAUCGCCUGCUCACUGCUACUAAUCUGGUUACUCUGCCAAACAGCAGGGGAGAGCACCUCUUACUAUUCUUAGUACAGACAGUCGCAAGGCAGACGGUGGAGCAUUGUCAAUACAGGCCACCUCGAAUCAGGGAAGAUCGUAACCGAAAAACAGCCAGUCCUGAAGAUUCAGAUAUGCCAGAUCAUGAUUUAGAGCCUCCAAGAUUUGCCCAGCUUGCAUUGGAGCGUGUUCUACAGGACUGGAAUGCCUUGAAAUCUAUGAUUAUGUUUGGGUCGCAGGAGAAUAAAGACCCUCUUAGUGCCAGCAGUAGAAUAGGCCAUCUUUUGCCAGAAGAGCAAGUAUACCUCAAUCAGCAAAGUGGCACAAUUCGGCUGGACUGUUUCACUCAUUGCCUUAUAGUUAAGUGUACAGCAGAUAUUUUGCUUUUAGAUACUCUACUAGGUACACUAGUGAAAGAACUCCAAAACAAAUAUACACCUGGACGUAGAGAAGAAGCUAUUGCUGUGACAAUGAGGUUUCUACGUUCAGUGGCAAGAGUUUUUGUUAUUCUGAGUGUGGAAAUGGCUUCAUCCAAAAAGAAAAACAACUUUAUUCCACAGCCAAUUGGAAAAUGCAAGCGUGUAUUCCAAGCAUUGCUACCUUACGCUGUGGAAGAAUUGUGCAACGUAGCAGAGUCACUGAUUGUUCCUGUCAGAAUGGGGAUUGCUCGUCCAACUGCACCAUUUACCCUGGCUAGUACUAGCAUAGAUGCCAUGCAGGGCAGUGAAGAAUUAUUUUCAGUGGAACCACUACCACCACGACCAUCAUCUGAUCAGUCUAGCAGCUCCAGUCAGUCUCAGUCAUCCUACAUCAUCAGGAAUCCACAGCAGAGGCGCAUCAGCCAGUCACAGCCCGUUCGGGGCAGAGAUGAAGAACAGGAUGAUAUUGUUUCAGCAGAUGUGGAAGAGGUUGAGGUGGUGGAGGGUGUGGCUGGAGAAGAGGAUCAUCAUGAUGAACAGGAAGAACACGGGGAAGAAAAUGCUGAGGCAGAGGGACAACAUGAUGAGCAUGAUGAAGACGGGAGUGAUAUGGAGCUGGACUUGUUAGCAGCAGCUGAAACAGAAAGUGAUAGUGAAAGUAACCACAGCAACCAAGAUAAUGCUAGUGGGCGCAGAAGCGUUGUCACUGCAGCAACUGCUGGUUCAGAAGCAGGAGCAAGCAGUGUUCCUGCCUUCUUUUCUGAAGAUGAUUCUCAAUCGAAUGACUCAAGUGAUUCUGAUAGCAGUAGUAGUCAGAGUGACGACAUAGAACAGGAGACCUUUAUGCUUGAUGAGCCAUUAGAAAGAACCACAAAUAGCUCCCAUGCCAAUGGUGCUGCCCAAGCUCCCCGUUCAAUGCAGUGGGCUGUCCGCAACACCCAGCAUCAGCGAGCAGCCAGUACAGCCCCUUCCAGUACAUCUACACCAGCAGCAAGUUCAGCGGGUUUGAUUUAUAUUGAUCCUUCAAACUUACGCCGGAGUGGUACCAUCAGUACAAGUGCUGCAGCUGCAGCAGCUGCUUUGGAAGCUAGCAACGCCAGCAGUUACCUAACAUCUGCAAGCAGUUUAGCCAGGGCUUACAGCAUUGUCAUUAGACAAAUCUCGGACUUGAUGGGCCUUAUUCCUAAGUAUAAUCACCUAGUAUACUCUCAGAUUCCAGCAGCUGUGAAAUUGACUUACCAAGAUGCAGUAAACUUACAGAACUAUGUAGAAGAAAAGCUUAUUCCCACUUGGAACUGGAUGGUCAGUAUUAUGGAUUCUACUGAAGCUCAAUUACGUUAUGGUUCUGCAUUAGCAUCUGCUGGUGAUCCUGGACAUCCAAAUCAUCCUCUUCACGCUUCUCAGAAUUCAGCGAGAAGAGAGAGGAUGACUGCGCGAGAAGAAGCUAGCUUACGAACACUUGAAGGCAGACGACGUGCCACCUUGCUUAGCGCCCGUCAAGGAAUGAUGUCUGCACGAGGAGACUUCCUAAAUUAUGCUCUGUCUCUAAUGCGGUCUCAUAAUGAUGAGCAUUCUGAUGUUCUUCCAGUUUUGGAUGUUUGCUCAUUGAAGCAUGUGGCAUAUGUUUUUCAAGCACUUAUAUACUGGAUUAAGGCAAUGAAUCAGCAGACAACAUUGGAUACACCUCAACUAGAACGCAAAAGGACGCGAGAACUCUUGGAACUGGGUAUUGAUAAUGAAGAUUCAGAACAUGAAAAUGAUGAUGACACCAAUCAAAGUGCUACUUUGAAUGAUAAGGAUGAUGACUCUCUUCCUGCAGAAACUGGCCAAAACCAUCCAUUUUUCCGACGUUCAGACUCCAUGACAUUCCUUGGGUGUAUACCCCCAAAUCCAUUUGAAGUGCCUCUGGCUGAAGCCAUCCCCUUGGCUGAUCAGCCACAUCUGUUGCAGCCAAAUGCUAGAAAGGAGGAUCUUUUUGGCCGUCCAAGUCAGGGUCUUUAUUCUUCAUCUGCCAGUAGUGGGAAAUGUUUAAUGGAGGUUACAGUGGAUAGAAACUGCCUAGAGGUUCUUCCAACAAAAAUGUCUUAUGCUGCCAAUCUGAAAAAUGUAAUGAACAUGCAAAACCGGCAAAAAAAAGAAGGGGAAGAACAGCCCGUGCUGCCAGAAGAAACUGAGAGUUCAAAACCAGGGCCAUCUGCUCAUGAUCUUGCUGCACAAUUAAAAAGUAGCUUACUAGCAGAAAUAGGACUUACUGAAAGUGAAGGGCCACCUCUCACAUCUUUCAGGCCACAGUGUAGCUUUAUGGGAAUGGUUAUUUCCCAUGAUAUGCUGCUAGGACGUUGGCGCCUUUCUUUAGAACUGUUCGGCAGGGUAUUCAUGGAAGAUGUUGGAGCAGAACCUGGAUCAAUCCUAACUGAAUUGGGUGGUUUUGAGGUAAAAGAAUCAAAAUUCCGCAGAGAAAUGGAAAAACUGAGAAACCAGCAGUCAAGAGAUUUGUCACUAGAGGUUGAUCGGGAUCGAGAUCUUCUCAUUCAGCAGACUAUGAGGCAGCUUAACAAUCACUUUGGUCGAAGAUGUGCUACUACACCAAUGGCUGUACACAGAGUAAAAGUCACAUUUAAGGAUGAGCCAGGAGAGGGCAGUGGUGUAGCACGAAGUUUUUAUACAGCCAUUGCACAAGCAUUUUUAUCAAAUGAAAAAUUGCCAAAUCUAGAGUGUAUCCAAAAUGCCAACAAAGGCACCCACACAAGUUUAAUGCAGAGAUUAAGGAACCGAGGAGAGAGAGACCGGGAAAGGGAGAGAGAAAGGGAAAUGAGGAGGAGUAGUGGUUUGCGAGCAGGUUCUCGGAGGGACCGGGAUAGAGACUUUAGAAGACAGCUUUCCAUCGACACUAGGCCCUUUAGACCAGCCUCUGAAGGGAAUCCUAGCGAUGAUCCUGAGCCUUUGCCAGCACAUCGGCAGGCACUUGGAGAGAGGCUUUAUCCUCGUGUACAAGCAAUGCAACCAGCAUUUGCAAGUAAAAUCACUGGCAUGUUGUUGGAAUUAUCCCCAGCUCAGCUGCUUCUCCUUCUAGCAAGUGAGGAUUCUCUGAGAGCAAGAGUGGAUGAGGCCAUGGAACUCAUUAUUGCACAUGGACGGGAAAAUGGAGCUGAUAGUAUCCUGGAUCUUGGAUUAGUAGACUCCUCAGAAAAGGUACAGCAGGAAAACCGAAAGCGCCAUGGCUCUAGUCGAAGUGUAGUAGAUAUGGAUUUAGAUGAUACAGAUGAUGGUGAUGACAAUGCCCCUUUGUUUUACCAACCUGGGAAAAGAGGAUUUUAUACUCCAAGGCCUGGCAAGAACACAGAAGCAAGGUUGAAUUGUUUCAGAAACAUUGGCAGGAUUCUUGGACUAUGUCUGUUACAGAAUGAACUAUGUCCUAUCACAUUGAAUAGACAUGUAAUUAAAGUAUUGCUUGGUAGAAAAGUCAAUUGGCAUGAUUUUGCUUUUUUUGAUCCUGUAAUGUAUGAGAGUUUGCGGCAACUAAUCCUCGCGUCUCAGAGUUCAGAUGCUGAUGCUGUUUUCUCAGCAAUGGAUUUGGCAUUUGCAAUUGACCUGUGUAAAGAAGAAGGUGGAGGACAGGUUGAACUCAUUCCUAAUGGUGUAAAUAUACCAGUCACUCCACAGAAUGUAUAUGAGUAUGUGCGGAAAUACGCAGAACACAGAAUGUUGGUAGUUGCAGAACAGCCCUUACAUGCAAUGAGGAAAGGUCUACUAGAUGUGCUUCCAAAAAAUUCAUUAGAAGAUUUAACGGCAGAAGAUUUUAGGCUUUUGGUAAAUGGCUGCGGUGAAGUCAAUGUGCAAAUGCUGAUCAGUUUUACCUCUUUCAAUGAUGAAUCAGGAGAAAAUGCUGAGAAGCUUCUGCAGUUCAAGCGUUGGUUCUGGUCAAUAGUAGAGAAGAUGAGCAUGACAGAACGACAAGAUCUUGUUUACUUUUGGACAUCAAGCCCAUCACUGCCAGCCAGUGAAGAAGGAUUCCAGCCUAUGCCCUCAAUCACAAUAAGACCACCAGAUGACCAACAUCUUCCUACUGCAAAUACUUGCAUUUCUCGACUUUACGUCCCACUCUAUUCCUCUAAACAGAUUCUCAAACAGAAAUUGUUACUCGCCAUUAAGACCAAGAAUUUUGGUUUUGUGUAGAGUAUAAAAAGUGUGUAUUGCUGUGUAAUAUUACUAGCAAAUUUUGUAGAUUUUUUUCCAUUUGUCUAUAAAAGUUUAUGGAAGUUAAUGCUGUCAUACCCCCCUGGUGGUACCUUAAAGAGAUAAAAUGCAGACAUUCCUUGCUGAGUUUAUAGCUUAAAGGCCUAAGGAGCACUAGCAACAUUUGGCUAUAUUGGUUUGCUAGUCACCAACUUCUGGGUCUAACCCCAGCCAAAGAUGACAGCAGAACAACAUAAUUUACACUGUGAUUUAUCUUUUUGCUGAGGGGGAAAAAAUGUAAAUGUUCUGAAAAUUCACUGCUGCCUUUGUGGAAACUGUUUCAGCAAAGGUUCUUGUAUAGAGGGAAUAGGGAAUUUCAAAAUAAAAAAUUAAGUAUGUUCUGUGUUUUCAUUUUAACUUUUUUUAUGGUGUUUAAUUUGUGGUUGGCUGCAACUGUGUAUCAUGUAUAUGGAACUUGUAAAAAAGUUCUCGACAUUCAGAUCUUAAGAGAUGAAAUCACUUUUACCUAUAAAAACCACUUUUAUUGCGGUUUGACUGCAUUGAGCUCUAGGAUAUUAAAUGAUAUCACUAAUAUUUUGCAUGUAAUUUGCUCAUUUGAGUGAGGGCACUUUUUUUGUACAUAUGAUGGGGCCAAUGCACAAUACUUUUAUCACAAUCAACUUUUUCUUUGUAUCCCUAUUUCAAUGAGCAGUCAGUCUCAAGAGGUUACUGCACUUCAGUUCUAACUAGACAUUUGUACUAAGGUAUUUCAGUUAUGUAAACUCAGCCUGGGCACUUUCUGAUAACUGUAAAAUGUUUUAUAAGAUCAUGAUUAUUGAAGAUACAUUUUGGAAAAUUUUAAAUGUUCGUGAGCAGCUUAACUACUUUUGUAUCUAGCCUUUUUUAAGUAUCUUGUUACAUUUACUUUUUUAAAUAAAGAAAUUACAGAAGAAAUGUCAAGUAAUAUUGAAGAAACAAUAGUUUUUAUUUAUGUAGUUGUACAUUUUUAAACUAAGGGCAAUACACUGACAUGGUUAUGUGCAUAAAAAUUUUGACUUAAAGAACUGGAAGUUUAUAUACACCUGGACUAUAAGAAACAGAAGAAAAUCAGUCCACAUUUUACAGUUAGCAGAGAAUCCUAAAUGGCACUGGCCUGGCCACCUUUUCAUUUUACAAAUGGGGGAAGUGAAGUGUGACCCCUUACUUGGCAUAGGAAGUUAACUUACACCUAAUAACUGACAGGUUUUUGUUUUGAUGACCUAUUAAUUAUGUAGCCUAGGAUUAAUAUCCCAAAAUUACUCUGGUUUAAGUAGCUUUAUUCAGUGGCAUAAUAACACUGUUUUCUUCCUUAAGUCUUCAAUGAAGUGACUUAAAACAGUCACUUUACAUAUUAAAAAUGAGGAGAGCAAUUCUCUGGAAUCUCUCCUUUCAGUUCCUUUGUAGGAUUUCUGGCCUUGAGGAUAGUCUUCAUGUUCAAAGGCACUAUGCUUUUAUUAUAUAACUUCCUUCAGAAGACUGAACCACAUGAUAUUCUCAGCCCUGUUAACACUAAAAAUAUUUAAAACUGAAUGAUAGUAGUGACUCAUUGUAUUACUUAAAACUUAUAUAACACGCUGUAUUAGAUGUGUGUAAAUUAGCCAAAGGUUAUUUUACAAAGUGAGACAUUGGUUUUUAUGUCUAAAUGCUAUUUCUGAAUAAAUGAAAUAGUAAUUAGAUCAAGAGCUGAUUAGCAUCAAUGUGUUUGAAAGAUAUAAAAUUUAUACAUCACCUUAACCUCUGUAUGCACAUGAUGGGAUUGAUAAAAUAUUAAAUGAGAACAAACUAGAUAUGAUUAGGACAUUUGAAACCCUAAUUGUGAAUUUAUUUUUAAUAGUUACUGAAAUGAAAAUAUUUAAAAUAAUGCACAAUGUCUUAAGUCUUCCUAAAUCAAGAUUUUGGUUAAAAAAUACUUCUAAUAAUAGUAAAAGAUUUUUUUUUUAAGUAAAUCAUAAAACGGUUCUAAAUGUAAAAUAAAGACAUGUAAAAUAAA